GCGGAAGUGGUGACCGUGAGAGAAGAAGAUGGCGGCCCCUGUAGUGGCGCCGCCUGGUGUGGUGGUUAGUCGGGCUAACAAGCGCAGCGGCGCGGGGCCGGGAGGCAGCGGUGGCGGGGGAGCCAGAGGGGCGGAGGAGGAACCGCCGCCGCCCCUACAAGCAGUUCUGGUGGCCGAUAGCUUCGAUCGCCGCUUCUUCCCCAUCUCCAAGGACCAGCCUCGGGUCCUCUUGCCCCUGGCCAAUGUGGCAUUAAUUGACUACACUCUGGAAUUCCUGACUGCCACAGGUGUACAGGAAACAUUUGUCUUUUGUUGCUGGAAAGCUGCUCAAAUCAAAGAACAUUUACUGAAGUCAAAGUGGUGCCGCCCUACAUCUCUCAAUGUGGUUCGAAUAAUUACAUCAGAGCUCUAUCGAUCACUGGGAGAUGUCCUCCGUGAUGUUGAUGCCAAGGCUUUGGUGCGCUCUGACUUUCUUCUGGUGUAUGGGGAUGUCAUCUCAAACAUCAAUAUCACCAGAGCCCUUGAGGAACACAGGUUGAGACGGAAGCUAGAAAAAAAUGUUUCUGUGAUGACGAUGAUCUUCAAGGAGUCAUCCCCCAGCCACCCAACUCGUUGCCACGAAGACAAUGUGGUAGUGGCUGUGGAUAGUACCACAAACAGGGUUCUCCAUUUUCAGAAGACCCAGGGUCUCCGGCGUUUUGCAUUUCCUCUGAGCCUGUUUCAGGGCAGUAGUGAUGGAGUGGAGGUUCGAUAUGAUUUACUGGAUUGUCAUAUCAGCAUCUGUUCUCCUCAGGUGGCACAACUCUUUACAGACAACUUUGACUACCAAACUCGAGAUGACUUUGUGCGAGGUCUCUUAGUGAAUGAGGAGAUCCUAGGGAACCAGAUCCACAUGCACGUAACAGCUAAGGAAUAUGGUGCCCGUGUCUCCAACCUACACAUGUACUCAGCUGUCUGUGCUGACGUCAUCCGCCGAUGGGUCUACCCUCUCACCCCAGAGGCGAACUUCACUGACAGCACCACCCAGAGCUGCACUCAUUCCCGGCACAACAUCUACCGAGGGCCUGAGGUCAGCCUGGGCCAUGGCAGCAUCCUAGAGGAAAAUGUGCUCCUGGGCUCUGGCACUGUCAUUGGCAGCAAUUGCUUUAUCACCAACAGUGUCAUUGGCCCCGGCUGCCACAUUGGUGAUAACGUGGUGCUGGACCAGACCUACCUGUGGCAGGGUGUUCGAGUGGCGGCUGGAGCACAGAUCCAUCAGUCUCUGCUUUGUGACAAUGCUGAGGUCAAGGAACGAGUGACACUGAAACCACGCUCUGUCCUCACUUCCCAGGUGGUCGUGGGCCCAAAUAUCACGCUGCCUGAGGGCUCGGUGAUCUCUUUGCACCCUCCAGAUGCAGAGGAAGAUGAAGAUGAUGGCGAGUUCAGUGAUGAUUCUGGGGCUGACCAAGAAAAGGACAAAGUGAAGAUGAAAGGUUACAAUCCAGCAGAAGUAGGAGCUGCUGGCAAGGGCUACCUCUGGAAAGCUGCAGGCAUGAACAUGGAGGAAGAGGAGGAACUGCAGCAGAAUCUGUGGGGACUCAAGAUCAACAUGGAAGAAGAGAGUGAAAGUGAAAGUGAGCAAAGUAUGGAUUCUGAGGAGCCGGACAGCCGGGGAGGCUCCCCUCAGAUGGAUGACAUCAAAGUGUUCCAGAAUGAAGUUUUAGGAACACUACAGCGGGGCAAAGAGGAGAACAUUUCUUGUGACAAUCUCGUCCUGGAAAUCAACUCUCUCAAGUAUGCCUAUAACAUAAGUCUAAAGGAGGUGAUGCAGGUACUGAGCCACGUGGUCCUGGAGUUCCCCCUGCAACAGAUGGAUUCCCCGCUUGACUCAAGCCGCUACUGUGCCCUGCUGCUUCCUCUGCUAAAGGCCUGGAGCCCUGUUUUUAGGAACUACAUAAAGCGCGCAGCCGACCAUUUGGAAGCGUUAGCAGCCAUUGAGGACUUCUUCCUAGAGCAUGAAGCUCUUGGUAUUUCCAUGGCCAAGGUACUGAUGGCUUUCUACCAGCUGGAGAUCCUGGCUGAGGAAACAAUUCUGAGCUGGUUCAGCCAAAGAGAUACAACUGACAAGGGCCAGCAGUUGCGCAAGAAUCAACAGCUGCAGAGGUUCAUCCAGUGGCUAAAAGAGGCAGAAGAGGAGUCAUCUGAAGAUGACUGAAGUCACACUGCCUGCUCCUUUGGGUGUGAUUGAGUGCCCUCCUGGCUCCUGGGCUGGGACAAGUGAGGAACUAGCUGCAGAGGGAUGAGUGACCACCAUCCAGGCUGAGACUGAAAGGAGCAGAGGCUGGAACUACAGUAUUCUUUCCCCUGCUAGCAACCAUGUGCCUCCCAUCCUGACUGUGGAGUUGGGAUGUGGAAGUGGGGCUGGAACAAAGCUUCUGCCUAGGGAGGAGCUAAGCAGGCCCGGCAGUUGGAGGAAGGCCAGAGGAACAGCUUUGUGCUCCGGCUUUCCCUCAGGGAACAGCAGAGAGCAGUUGGCUCUUUCUGCUGCUUGUAUAUGUUAAUAUUAAAAGAGAGAGUGGUGUA